CCACAAAUGUGGGAGGGCGAUAACCACUCGUAGAAAGCGUGAGAAGUUACUACAAGCGGUCCUCCCGGCCACCGUACUGUUCCGCUCCCAGAAGCCCCGGGCGGCGGAAGUCGUCACUCUUAAGAAGGGACGGGGCCCCACGCUGCGCACCCGCGGGUUUGCUAUGGCGAUGAGCAGCGGCGGCAGUGGUGGCGGCGUCCCGGAGCAGGAGGAUUCCGUGCUGUUCCGGCGCGGCACAGGCCAGAGCGAUGAUUCUGACAUUUGGGAUGAUACAGCACUGAUAAAAGCAUAUGAUAAAGCUGUGGCUUCAUUUAAGCAUGCUCUAAAGAAUGGUGACAUUUGUGAAACUUCGGGUAAACCAAAAACCACACCUAAAAGAAAACCUGCUAAGAAGAAUAAAAGCCAAAAGAAGAAUACUGCAGCUUCCUUACAACAGUGGAAAGUUGGGGACAAAUGUUCUGCCAUUUGGUCAGAAGACGGUUGCAUUUACCCAGCUACCAUUGCUUCAAUUGAUUUUAAGAGAGAAACCUGUGUUGUGGUUUACACUGGAUAUGGAAAUAGAGAGGAGCAAAAUCUGUCCGAUCUACUUUCCCCAAUCUGUGAAGUAGCUAAUAAUAUAGAACAAAAUGCUCAAGAGAAUGAAAAUGAAAGCCAAGUUUCAACAGAUGAAAGUGAGAACUCCAGGUCUCCUGGAAAUAAAUCAGAUAACAUCAAGCCCAAAUCUGCUCCAUGGAACUCUUUUCUCCCUCCACCACCCCCCAUGCCAGGGCCAAGACUGGGACCAGGAAAGCCAGGUCUAAAAUUCAAUGGCCCACCACCGCCACCGCCACCACCACCACCCCACUUACUAUCAUGCUGGCUGCCUCCAUUUCCUUCUGGACCACCAAUAAUUCCCCCACCACCUCCCAUAUGUCCAGAUUCUCUUGAUGAUGCUGAUGCUUUGGGAAGUAUGUUAAUUUCAUGGUACAUGAGUGGCUAUCAUACUGGCUAUUAUAUGGAAAUGCUGGCAUAGAGCAGCACUAAAUGACACCACUAAAGAAACGAUCAGACAGAUCUGGAAUGUGAAGCGUUAUAGAAGAUAACUGGCCUCAUUUCUUCAAAAUAUCAAGUGUUGGGAAAGAAAAAAGGAAGUGGAAUGGGUAACUCUUCUUGAUUAAAAGUUAUGUAAUAACCAAAUGCAAUGUGAAAUAUUUUACUGGACUCUAUUUUGAAAAACCAUCUGUAAAAGACUGGGGUGGGGGUGGGAGGCCAGCACGGUGGUGAGGCAGUUGAGAAAAUUUGAAUGUGGAUUAGAUUUUGAAUGAUAUUGGAUAAUUAUUGGUAAUUUUAUGAGCUGUGAGAAGGGUGUUGUAGUUUAUAAAAGACUGUCUUAAUUUGCAUACUUAAGCAUUUAGGAAUGAAGUGUUAGAGUGUCUUAAAAUGUUUCAAAUGGUUUAACAAAAUGUAUGUGAGGCGUAUGUGGCAAAAUGUUACAGAAUCUAACUGGUGGACAUGGCUGUUCAUUGUACUGUUUUUUUCUAUCUUCUAUAUGUUUAAAAGUAUAUAAUAAAAAUAUUUAAUUUUUUUUUAAA